GGGCCGGCCAGGGUGCCGCAGACGCGGGGACGCUGGCUCGCUCCCUCCCUCCCUCCCUCCGACGCUGUGAGUAGAGAAGCUAGGCCCCGAGCCGGGCGGGACUAGGGUGGUGGUUGUGUUCUGCCCUCGCCCGUCGCCAACGCUGGGCUGACUGAAAACCUGGCCCUUUGGGUCGCGCGUCUUCGACCUUCACCGCCAUGCGGACAUGGGGCCGUGGGAGAAACUCUGGGCGGGAUUACGGUGAAAAUUCUUGUUUGGGCGGGCCCUGCGGCUUCUUUCUUCCGGCUCGCCCUCGGCCCCGCCCCCGCCCCGCCCCCGCUCCAGCUCCAGCCGGGUCCUCGCUCGGCCCCGCACGCGGCCCGCGGUAGACGGAGGGCCUGGGCACCCACCGUCUCCAUCCCGGCCCCAGCCCAGUCGAGCGUCCACUAGAAGGGCGCUCCCUGUCCGGCCCUAAUCCUCGCUCCUCACGGAGGCUCUUUGUCACAGCGAAGACUGACAGCCCGCAGUCUUCUGGACUUCUUUUAUGGGGCUCCUGGCGGUGCUAUUCAUUCAGUCAUUGAUUCGUCUUGUAAAUAUGGAGCGCCUGCUCUGUACUCGACCCGGCACUGGGUACCGGAAGAACCAGACAGCUCGGUUUUUGCCACCAUUUAUAAGUCUGUGUCCUUUUCUUGAGUACUGAACCGAGAUACAGUUUUAAAUGUGCUGUGCGGUCUCUGAGCAGCGACUCACCUGUGCAGGUCACUUCACCUGAUUCCCUUUAUGUAAAAAUGAGGGCGAUGGGCUGUGUAAUCUCUAAAGGACCUUCUAACUCUUUAAAAUUGUCACUGUGCCGGUGUUGCUAACACUCAUUCUGUAUGCUUGAUGGCAGUUUUUAAUUUUUAGGGUUAGGACAGCUGAACAUAACAAAUAGAAUUAUACAGAUUUAUUACCAGAAGGACUUCGUGUGCCUCUAAGAAUCUUGGUUCCAGUCUUUGGUCAGGUAGCUCCAGGAAAUCACUUCACCUCUUUGCCUCAGACCCUCCUCAGUGAACUAGGAAUGAUAGCAGUGUCUCCCUAGUCUUAGGGCCGUUGAGCGGAUUACACGAGAUAAGGUCAGCAGGUGUUUAGCACAGUGAAGCAUUUGCUACGUGAUGACAUUUAUUAUGGUUAAAGGGUUUUACCACCAGAACAGUGGUACAUAGUUUGCUUUAUUUGUUAAAACAAUGUAGAAUAUUGCCUGCUUGUUCCAUCACAGAUGAAAAAAAGAGAUGGUUAUUCAACUUUGUGAGGUAAUUGUGGAUUUCCAUGCAAUUGUAAGAAUAGAGAUUCUGUGUACCCUUUACCCAGUCUUCCCAGUGGUAGCAUCUUGCAAAACUAGUACCAUAUCACAACCAGGUAAUUGACAUUCACACAAUCCAUUGAUCUCAUUCAGAUUCCUCAUUUUGUAUUAGUGUUCUCUGUGUAUAUUUAGUUCUAUAUGGUUAUCAGGUGUGUAGAUUCUUGUAUCCACCACCACAGUCAAGGUACAGCCCAGGUCCAUCACCACAAGGGUCCCUCCAGUUGCCCUUUUAUAACCACAACUUACCUUUGCAGCCCCACCCAAUCUAUUCUCUGUUUCUAAAAUUUUGUUAUAUCAAGAAUGUUACAUAAAUGUAAUUAUUGUAAUUAUACAGUAUGUAACUUUUAUUGACUCUUUUUCAUUCAGCAUAAUCCCUUGAGAUAUAUCCAAACUGUUACAUGUAUCAGUAGUUCCUUCCUUUUUAUUACUGAGUGGUAUUCCAUAAUGUAGAUGUACUACAGUAUUGAUAUGGUUUGGCUGUGUCCCCACCCAAAUCUCAUCUUGAAUUGUAACUCACCAUUCCCAUGUGUUGUGGGAGGAACCAGGUGGGAGGUGAUUGAAUUAUGGAGGCAGGUCCUUCCUGUGCUGUUCUCCAGAUAGUGAAUGAGCCUCACAAGAUGUGAUGGUUUUAAAAACGGGAGGUUUCCCUGCACAAGUUCUUUCUUUGCAUGCUGCCAUCCAUGUAAGAUGUGACUUGCUCCUCCUUGCCUUCCACCAUGAUUGUGAGGCCUCCCCAGCCAUGUGGAACUAUCAAAUGAUGCCGUUUGGAAAAAUUUCCCAGCAGUUGUGUGGCGUAAAGAAACUCCCAUGGUCAUGUGACUCCAGAUACUUCUGGGGCUGGUUGAAUGCAGUGUUUAAUAAGGUGGAUUAUGAUCGCAUCAGGGAUGUUGGCCCUGACAGGGCGGCAUCCGAGUGGUUGCUGCGCUGUGGGGCCAUGGUGCGCUACCAUGGCCAGGAGAGGUGGCAGAAGGACUACAACCACCUUCCAACAGGCCCUCUGGACAAAUACAAGAUUCAGGCGAUCGACGCCACCGACUCUUGUAUCAUGAGCAUUGGAUUUGAUCACAUGGAGGGCCUAGAGCAUGUUGAAAAAAUAAGGCUGUGCAAGUGUCAUUAUAUCGAGGAUGACUGUUUGCUGAGACUUAGUCAACUUGAAAAUUUACAAAAAACCAUAUUGGAAAUGGAAAUAAUAUCCUGUGGGAAUAUCACAGACAAAGGCAUCAUUGCUUUGCGUCAUUUAAGAAACCUCAAAUAUUUGUUGUUAAGUGAUCUUCCUGGAGUAAGAGAAAAAGAAAAUCUUGUCCAAGCCUUUAAGACAGCACUGCCUUCUCUGGAACUAAAAUUACAAUUGAAGUAAAAUAAUGUGUCUUAUUUCAGUAUAAAGGAUCAUUUGAAACUGUUGAUUCCAAACAUCAACUAAUAUUAUAUAGUCAUCAGUAGAAUUAUAAGGAUGCCAUAUCAUGACAUUUUAGAAGUGGAGAGUGCAUCAUAUGUAGAAAAUAAAUAUUCAGACGUGGCUCAUUAAUGUUACUAAGUUGGAAGUGAGAAUUUAUGAACAUUAAUUCAUUUUAAGAAAAGUGCAGCCAGGCGCAGUGGCUCAUGCCUGUAAUCCUAGCACUUUGGGAGGCCAAAGCGGGCAGAUCACCUGAGGUCAGGAGUUCAAGACCAACCAUGGCCAACAUGGUGAAACCCCAUCUCUACUAAAAAAACAAAAUUAGCUGAAUGUGGUGGUGCACGCCUUUAAUCCCAGCUACUCUGGAGGCUGAGGCAGGAGAAUCACUUGACUUGGGAGGUGGAGGUUGCAGGGACCCGAGAUUGUGCCACUGCACUCCAGCCUGGGUGACAGAGCGAGACUGUCUCAAAAAAAAAAAAAAAAGAAAAAUGUAAACUAGGUAACAUUUUAAUUCUAAUAUAUUCAUUUAAUAUGUAAAUCUAUAGAUAUCUCUUGAUGUAGAUAUUUAGAAUCCUUUAAAGUUAUUUGUACAACAGAUGUUUUUAUUAUAACAGUAAUUUACAUUUAACUUUAAAGUUAGUGAAGCAUACUACCAUAAAUGCACAAUUAUGAAAAAUUAGAAGCUAAAUUACAGAUUCAUUGAUGGAGUCAAUUAUGCAAAGUGGUCAGUGGUUGUUGAAGCAUGCAUUGCUUCAACAGGAUUUGCGUGCAUUUCCCAUGAUCCUGCAUUCUUGUGUUCUUGAUAGCAUACAGACUUACUCAGAAUCAACAGUUGCUGCUUAAUUUGUCUAUUUUGUAAGCUUAGGCUACUAUUUUAUUAAAACUGGACAUAGAUACUUGGCUGAAUACAAAUAGUUUUGCAGAUUGCAAUAUAAUAAAGGAAACAGUAAAAACUAGUGGGCUAUGCUUAGGUUUUUCUUGAAACCUAACAUUGCUUUAGGCUGGGUGCCGUGGCUCGUGCCUGUAAUCCCAGUGCUUUGGGAGGCUGAGGUGGGAGGAUCACUUGAGACCAGGAGUUUGAGACCAAUUUGGGCAACACAGUGAGACCCCAUCUCUAAAAAAAUUUUAAAAAUUAGGCAGGCAUGGUGGUGCAUACCUGUAAUCUCAGAUACUUGGGAGGUUGAGGUGGUAGGAUUGCUUGAGCUCAGGAGUUUGAGGCUGCAGUAAGCUAUGAUCACGGCCACUGCACACCAGCCUGGUAGCCUGGGUGAAAGGGGGAGACCCUGUCUCUUAAAAAAAAGGGCUGGCCUGUAAUCCCAGCACUUUUGAAGGCCAAGGCAGGCAGAUCAUUUGAGCCCAGGAGUUCAGGACGAGCCUGGGCAACAUGGCAAAACCCUGUCUCUACCAAAAAAUUAAAAAAUAAAAAAUAGCUGGGUGUAGUGGCACAUGCCUGUAGUCCCAACUACUCAGGAGUCUGAGGUAGGAGGAUCAGUUGAGCCCGGGAAGUCGAGGCUGCAGUGAGCCAUGUUGGCACCACUGCACUCCAGCCUGGGCAACAGAUUAAGACCCUGUCUCAAAAAAAAAAAAAAAAGUGAAAAAUAGAUAAAACAGGUCUUCAUUGUUACCUGUGAGAAAUGGCCCUGAUUCUAUUACUCUUAUAUGCCAGUUUGUUUAUAGAUUUCUGUGUGUUUGAUUUGAACUUUUUUUUUUUUUUUUUUUUUUUUGAGACAGACUCUCACUCUGUUGCCCAGGUUGGAGUGCAGUGGUGUGAUCUCAGUUCACUGCAACCUCUGCCUCCCGGGUUCAAGCAGUUCUCUGUCGCAGCGUCCCAGGUAGCUGGGAUUACAGGCGCCCACCACCACGCCCAGCUAAUUUUUGUACUUUUAGUAGAGACAGGGUUUCACCAUCUUGGCCAGACUGGUCUUGAACUCCUAACCUCAGGAUCCACCCGCCUCGGCCUCCCAAAGUGCUGGGAGCCACCGCGCCCAGCCUGGUUUGAACAUUAUUAAGCUGUUGAAUAUAAACUUGAAAAUAAUUUUCUAUGAUACAGCUUUCAGGUAGAAAAAUGAAUUUUCGUUGUGUUUAACAAUGUUGUGUUUAACAGCUUAUACAAAUAACACAGUAUAAAUGGUAAUUGCCACUGUCAUUUUAAAAAUCAGAAAAUAGUAAAUAAAAGGAUGUGGAAGAGUCUCAUGUGA